AAUGGCAAGCAGAAUGAUGUGGACAGUGUCUCAGCAGAGGAGGUACAAUGUACAAAAGAGGGAGACAUUAGUUCUUGUUGGGGGAAGGAGACAAGCUUCAUGGAGGAAAUGCCAUUUGAGUAGAGCCAGGGAAACUGGAUAGAUGGAAAAAUUAGAAGAAAGGGGAAUUCCACAUGGAGAGAAUCAUAUGAAUAAAGGCAUAGAGAUGGGAACUUACAAGGCCUACUUAAGAAACUGUAAGUAAUCUGGUGUGAAUGCAGCAUAUGUUGUGUAAAGAUAAAGCUAGAAAGAGAUAGGUAAAAGCUAUGAUUUAGGAAGGUUCAGUUGUUUUGACUUGGUUUUGACUUUGAAUUGGUAGCUAUGGAAUGUCUUAGGUCAGAGGACUGUCCUUUCUUAAUUCUUUUUCAGGGUCAAGACCUGUCUUUAUUAAGCCAUUAUUUCUCAGAAGUUGAAGUCACCCUAAAGAUACUUCUAAAUUAGACAUUGGUUAGGGGAAUCAGCAUUAGAGCACUCUUCUGGUCAUAAUGUGAUGUUAUGAUGAUGAUGCUCAUUGGUGAAGUCACAUUAAGGACUGCUUUUAGGGUUAUAGUGGCAGAAAGCAGUAGGAGGAAAAAUAUCGACUUUACUUCAGAUUGUAAAGAAGUGUGCUAUUAGAGGAGUACACUGCAUUCUCUCACCAACAGGUCUCCAGUGCUCAUUUUGUGGGAUAAUGUGUGGCCAGAGAGAAGAUGGUGAUAAUUAGCACCAUGGAGCCUCAGGUGUCAAAUGGUCCGACAUCCAAUACAAGCAAUGGACCCUCCAGCAACAACAGAAACUGUCCUUCUCCCAUGCAAACAGGGGCAACCACAGAUGACAGCAAAACCAACCUCAUCGUCAACUAUUUACCCCAGAAUAUGACCCAAGAAGAAUUCAGGAGUCUCUUCGGGAGCAUUGGUGAAAUAGAAUCCUGCAAACUUGUGAGAGACAAAAUUACAGGACAGAGUUUAGGGUAUGGAUUUGUUAACUAUAUUGAUCCAAAGGAUGCAGAGAAAGCCAUCAACACUUUAAAUGGACUCAGACUCCAGACCAAAACCAUAAAGGUCUCAUAUGCCCGUCCGAGCUCUGCCUCAAUCAGGGAUGCUAACCUCUAUGUUAGCGGCCUUCCCAAAACCAUGACCCAGAAGGAACUGGAGCAACUUUUCUCGCAAUACGGCCGUAUCAUCACCUCACGAAUCCUGGUUGAUCAAGUCACAGGAGUGUCCAGAGGGGUGGGAUUCAUCCGCUUUGAUAAGAGGAUUGAGGCAGAAGAAGCCAUCAAAGGGCUGAAUGGCCAGAAGCCCAGCGGUGCUACGGAACCGAUUACUGUGAAGUUUGCCAACAACCCCAGCCAGAAGUCCAGCCAGGCCCUGCUCUCCCAGCUCUACCAGUCCCCCAACCGGCGCUACCCAGGUCCACUUCACCACCAGGCUCAGAGGUUCAGGCUGGACAAUUUGCUUAAUAUGGCCUAUGGCGUAAAGAGGUUCUCCCCAAUUACCAUUGAUGGAAUGACAAGCCUUGUGGGAAUGAACAUCCCUGGUCACACAGGAACUGGGUGGUGCAUCUUUGUCUACAACCUGUCCCCCGAUUCCGAUGAGAGUGUCCUCUGGCAGCUCUUUGGCCCCUUUGGAGCAGUGAACAACGUAAAGGUGAUUCGUGACUUCAACACCAACAAGUGCAAGGGAUUCGGCUUUGUCACCAUGACCAACUAUGAUGAGGCGGCCAUGGCCAUCGCCAGCCUCAACGGGUACCGCCUGGGAGACAGAGUGUUGCAAGUUUCCUUUAAAACCAACAAAGCCCACAAGUCCUGAAUUUCCCAUUCUUACUUACUAAAAUAUAUAUAGAAAUAUAUACGAACAAAACACACGCGCGCACACACACACAUACACGAAAGAGAGAGAAACAAACUUUUCAAGGCUUAUAUUCAACCAUGGACUUUAUAAGCCAGUGUUGCCUAAGUAUUAAAACAUUGGAUUAUCCUGAGGUGUACCAGGAAAGGAUUUUAUAAUGCUUAGAAAAAAAGAAAAAAAAAAAACAAAAAAUACCUUUGAUGCAUUGAAUGUUCUUUCAUAGCUGUCGUUGUUGAAUAUAAUAUACAUAGAUAGCGAUGUGCAGGGAUUUUUACCCAGCCAGCUAACUUUACUACCUUCCUUGAAGGUGGAUCUUUUUAAGAUGACCAUUCGCUCAUUUGAAGAAGAAAAACAAAAAACAAAAAAAAUAAUAAAAAUAAAACAAUUUUUACAAAGUAAUGGGAUUCAAAGAAAGGAAAAAAAGAUUUUUCUUUUUUGUCAAAAUAUCGAUCCAAUCAGAUUGGUAAAAACCCCCACACAAAUUAAAGAGGAAUAAUAAAAAUUGCAAAAAUAAAAAAAAACUUUUGCAAAUUUUUUUAUUUUUCCUUCUUUCUUUUAUAUCAUGUGAACUAAAACAGUCUUCUGUUAGGGGAUGGGGGCAAGGGGGAUACCUGAUGACAUUAACAAUUUAAUAACAUUAACAUUGUUGCCAAAGAGGUGGUCUCUUUGCUGAAAAUGGGUUUCAAGAAAAAUCUAUUUUUAUAAAAUAUAAAGAAUUUUUACAAGAGAAUCUGGAUUUGAGAAAAAAAUAUUUUGACUGGCUAAUUUAGGGGAAAUUGACAACUUUGUCGCGUUCAUACUGCACUGGUAACUUUUUAGAGAUCAAGAUGUGUGUUUUAAACUGGAUUCGUAGACUGUUUUUUGAAGGAUGGGCUAUAAACAGAUGAUCUUCAUAUCUUUUCAUAGCAUGUAAUAAUAAUUAAAAAACAAUUAUUAAUUACUAGGGGAAAGGAGUGUUCGUUCUACCCAGGGUACCACAGUUCCCCACAGUCAAAACCCAAAAGCAAGGAGAUGAGUUGAAAGACAGUUUUUCUUUAAGUCAUCAGUAUGGGAUGUCAGCAGAACAAAAAUUAAAAAGAUUAAUUUUCCUUUUGAUCUAAAACUUCCUUAGUUUGAGCAGUAGGUGCUACAAAAUUAUUUACAUAUCUUAGUAUCAUAGUUAAAUGUAAUGUGUUUAGGAGAGGAAAACAAAAGAUACAUUUGCUUUAAAUUCAUUAAGAAAUUUUCAAAUUCACUUUGUAGCCCAUGCUGAUAGAAUUGGGCUGUGUUGGUACAUUUGAAACACUGUUUAUGUUGCUUGAAACACUUAUUUAUUUAAUCGCCGAUGUGAUGAUGCCUAUGGCCGAGAUCAAAUAUAGCUAGAUUGGCUAGACUACUUAUUUGUUUACUUAAACUAUGGGAAGAAGCAUAUUAUUGUGUCAUUCUGUUGUGUGUGUAUGUGUAUAUACAAUAUAAAUAUAUAUAUAUAAAGUUAUUUUUUCUUUGGGUUAAUUUAUUAUAAGUUGUAACACUUGGCUAGUUUUGUUUGUAUAUGUCUUAAAAUGUUUUCUUAUGAUAUUUAAGUGACAGUUAAAGAGGUAUCAAGGUAACUUGUGUAGAACUAUUCUUUGAUAUAUUGUCAUGUUUGUUGUGAAUAUUUUUUCUUACUGCACAGUAGAAAAAUAAAAACAACUGAGUCUUUAUUUUAAUGUAACUCAGAUUGGGGAAAACAAAACAGAGCUAAGGGAACAAAAUGACUGAGGGAGCACUCUCCCACGUCCAGUGCACUGAUCAUUUUAGUAUGUUUGUGCUUUGUACGGUUAUAUAUUUAAAACGAAAACAAAACAAAAAAAUACAAGGGUUCAUGCUCUUCCCUGGGUAAUAGAAACAGUUACUCGCUAUGCAUAAUCUAGUUGAUAGUUAAAUUUGCUAUUGCUUUUCUUGUCUUGUUAUAUAAAAUCUUUUCAAUACAAGUUUAGUCUUAAUGGUAAUAAAACGUUAUGGUUAUUUAUAACUUGUGCUUAUUUUGUGCAUUUUUUCCCAUGCUGAACCCACUAAGUGCAUGUAGACAGGACUGUUGUUUUCACACUGAAAAGGCAAACUUUGUAGUAGUCGUUGUAGUGGUAGACAGAUAACGAAUACCAAGGCUGCAUCAUAGACUCCUCCUUUAAAUUUUUUUUCUGUUUUUUUUUCCUCUUUUCGGUUUUGGAUAUAACACCAGAUUUCAGUUCAGAGAACACUCGUUCAACAUUCAGGGAAAGCUUUUUACGUCACCUGCUAUGAAUGAACGUAGUUUGCUGGCAAAGUUUUGAUGCAUUUGCUAAGCAUUAGUGGGAAAGGCAUGCCAAAAUCUUCUCUAUAAUGUGUUCAAUCUUGGGGGAAAAAAAAAGGAAAAAAAAUCUUAGGACCAGGCAGUUGUAUACUUUAGUUAUUAAUGAAUGACUUCAUGUUAAUCUUGCUAGUUUAGAUGAUUUCCAAGGGAAAGUAUUGUAAAUGUUUUUUUUUCAUAAUCUUGUUGUGUUUGAAUUAUUUGUACUUUAUCUGUCCAGACAAUAAAUGAAAGUGUGUAGAAUGGA